ACUGCAACGCGGAGGAGCAGGAUGGAGAUCCCUGUGCCUGUGCAGCCGUCUUGGCUGCGCCGCGCCUCGGCCCCGUUGCCCGGACUUUCGGCGCCCGGACGCCUCUUUGACCAGCGCUUCGGCGAGGGGCUGCUGGAGGCCGAGCUGGCUGCGCUCUGCCCCACCACGCUCGCCCCCUACUACCUGCGCGCACCCAGCGUGGCGCUGCCCGUCGCCCAGGUGCCGACGGACCCCGGCCACUUUUCGGUGCUGCUAGACGUGAAGCACUUCUCGCCGGAGGAAAUUGCUGUCAAGGUGGUGGGCGAACACGUGGAGGUGCACGCGCGCCACGAGGAGCGCCCGGAUGAGCACGGAUUCGUCGCGCGCGAGUUCCACCGUCGCUACCGCCUGCCGCCUGGCGUGGAUCCGGCUGCCGUGACGUCCGCGCUGUCCCCCGAGGGCGUCCUGUCCAUCCAGGCCGCACCAGCGUCGGCCCAGGCCCCACCGCCAGCCGCAGCCAAGUAGGAGGGGGCUGGGCCGCGCCCGCACCCCGGGAGCCUCCUCAGGCUCCCUCUAUUAAAGCCGAUCUGACUCCGCCCAGCCAGAUGUCCCGAGUGCGCCAAGGACUGUCCUCUCACCCACUCCUGGAUUCUGCCCUGACCUCCAUCCUGGACACUGCCUUGAUAACAUAGACCCUUCCACUGACACCCUCGCUCUCACACCCCCUCCAGCUUUCCGACCCCACACCGACAACUCCCCGGCUUCCAGACCCUACCAGCACUACCCUAACCCUCAGCCGACAGUCUCAGCCCCACCGACCCACUUUCUUGGCAUAUAGCCCCACUUAAGACCCCUCCUCUACUUCCUUCUGAGUCCUCUACAAAGACAUCCGGGUACUACAUUUCCAUCCCUUCCCUAUUUUGACACCAAAUUAUGGUGUAGACAGCCCUCCCCCAACCCCAGGCCAGUCAGGCACAAUCCCCCCACCCCCCAAACGUCCUGGACUGCACAGACCUCCCACUCCAGACCAUCCAGGCCUGGUUCCCAAGACCCGAUCCUUCCCCUGCAACCAGACAGUCUACAACUGCCCCCUCCAGCCCAUUUUCUGCCGUGAAACCCCAGCCAGCCACACCAGACUCUGGAACCCUUUUUCGACUGCCCCAACUCUUGGACACCAGGCCAACUAGAACACCCAACACCAAACUGUACAGACUCUCCCACCCCAACCUCCCCAGACUCUGCACGGAUGUCCUAGGCCCCCUCCCCAACUCUAACCAGACCCCAUCCCCCUAAGUCCCUUUGUCUUGACCCCCAAGUCUUCAACCAGAUAUCCUCGGCAACCCACCUCCCACCCUCCUCCUCUUCUCCUUCAAGACCCAACUGAGCACCCGCUCUGAUUCCCCACAGCCUUUCUCCCUGCCACCACUCCCUUAGUCUUUCCCAGGCUUACUCUCCCAAUAAAUGUGCUAGAGCUCUGCCAA